CCGGGCGCCCCGCAUUCCUCUCGCGUUUCUCGGGCUGCACGAUUCCGGCUGCCCUGUCUGCCUGGCGGUGCCUCUCGGGUCUGAGCUUAAAGCGGGUGGGUGCAAACCUUUGGGCAUCCAGGGAGAGCUUUCUUGUUAGAGCCCACACACAAUCGGGCGCAUCAAGUGGGUUGAAGAAAUAUGGAGAUCAACACAAAACUGCUCAUCAGUGUUACCUGUAUCAGCUUUUUCACCUUUCAGCUUCUUUUCUACUUUGUAAGUUACUGGUUUUCAGCAAAAGUUUCUCCAGGUUUCAAUAGUCUCAGCUUCAAAAAGAAGAUUGAAUGGAACUCAAGGGUAGUAUCCACAUGCCAUUCUUUGGUGGUUGGUAUUUUUGGCCUGUACAUUUUCUUAUUCGAUGAGGCUACUAAAGCUGAUCCACUUUGGGGUGGUCCAUCACUUGCAAACGUGAAUAUUGCUAUUGCCUCAGGCUACCUCAUUUCUGAUUUGUCCAUUAUAAUUUUGUAUUGGAAAGUGAUUGGUGACAAAUUUUUUAUAAUGCAUCAUUGUGCGUCCCUGUAUGCAUACUACCUUGUACUGAAAAAUGGAGUGCUGGCAUACAUUGGGAAUUUUCGCCUGCUUGCAGAGCUUUCCAGCCCGUUUGUGAAUCAGCGACCAAAGGCUGUAGUCACUGGAAACAUGGACUUGUUUUCAUCUCUAACUCUCCACCUCUCCACACUCAGCCUGCAGAGCCCGGCCAACAAUCAAGACAGAUGGGACCGUGUUCAGAAUUCACACAAAAGCUGAAGGAUUUAUGGAUGUGGAUAUACCUCUGGAAUUGGUGUUCCAUUUGCCAGUCAAUUAUCCUUCAUGUCUACCUGGUAUCUCGAUUAACUCUGAACAGUUGACCAGGGCCCAGUGUGUGACUGUGAAAGAGAAUUUACUUGAGCAAGCAGAGAGCCUUUUGUCGGAGCCUAUGGUUCAUGAGCUGGUUCUCUGGAUUCAGCAGAAUCUCAGGCAUAUCCUCAGCCAACCAGAAACUGGCAGUGGCAGUGAAAAGUGUACUUUUUCAACAAGCACGACCAUGGAUGAUGGAUUGUGGAUAACUCUUUUGCAUUUAGAUCACAUGAGAGCAAAGACUAAAUAUGUCAAAAUUGUGGAGAAGUGGGCUUCAGAUUUAAGGCUGACAGGAAGACUGAUGUUCAUGGGUAAAAUAAUACUGAUUUUACUACAGGGAGACAGAAACAACCUCAAGGUGCCAAAAAGUUAAAUGUUGAGUAUGAAUCUGGCUAUUUUCUGCUUUAAAUGGUGUGUCUUUAAGUGUGUUUUAUAACAAUGGGAUAGAUUAAUUAUUAAGAUGUUUCUGCUUUCAUUAUUACAAUCUUAAUGGAUCUUCCUUUUCUUUUUAAAGAAUGUCUGACUGCUAAUUACAAGUACAAACUUGCAAAGCUUGAAGAAUAAGAUUGCAUUUUAAAAAUCAUGUCACUUAAUAAAGUGACAGGUUAUUUAAAA